GCAGGUGUUCUUCAGUCAGCCAAAUGGAUCUCUGUUCCUUGCUCUCUUCUUGGCUGGGUGUCUGUGUUCAGAUCCAUGACACCUUGUGUCCCAAGUUCCCUGCACCCCCAUCUGCUAGCUGACAUUUUCUUGUGGCUACCUGUGUCAUGAUUGUAGUCAUUGUCAUUGUCUAUACUUAUGGGGACAAUGGGCUCUUCUUACUCACUCCUUCUAGUUUGUUUGUUUGUUUGUUUGUUUAAUGAUAUUAACUUUCUUGCCCAUGGGCUGUUGUGUGCUGAGUCGUUCUGCAUCAGUGCUGAUCACUCACAUGUUCUGUCUUUCUGGUAGGACUUGGCUUCAUGAAGGUCCCACAUAGCUAGACAACUGAGGGUGUGCAGAGAAACCUGGUUGCUUUAUAGGGUGAACAUGGUCUCAGAGAAGGCCUGGGCUUGUUGAGUGGCAACUGGUUGGGGGCAUGAUAUCCGGGCUGUUUUCCGAUCACAUAAGGAGCCUGUCCUGUCUUCACCACUGUUUGGGUGCACAUGCCACUGGCCAAAUCUCAUUUCUAUAUUUUCUUCUCAGUACUUGACACUUCUCUCUCUUAUUAUUUUUAUCUAUGACUUCUAGCACCUGGCUACCUCCACCUUUCUGAUCUUCAUGCAUCAUCUGCUUCUCUGCACUGCUCCCUCUGCAAUGUUUUCCAACAUUGACACACACAUAAUGUCUCAUGAAGUAUGUAUAUAUGACCACAUGAAGAUAUGUGAUCAUAUCACUUGCUACUCAGUUUCAAUUGUAUUUUCCUGGGCUUGGGCACAGUCAACCUUCUGCACAGCAUGCAGGUGUCACCAGCAGACAAGGUCCUCCUGAAGACUAUGUGGUUGUGGCCAUGGAACAGAGGAUGAAGAGACACCUUCUGACCAGAAUGUUUCUGUAGGAGUGUCACAGUCAAAGGCAGGUUCAUCCACACAGAAGACUCAAUCCUGUGAGAUGUGUGUCCCAGUCCUGAAAGAUAUUUUGCAUCUAGCUGAUCUCCCUGGGCAGAAACCAUACUUGGUUGGAGAAUGUACAAACCAUCACCAGCACCAGAAGCAUCACAGUGCAAAGAAAUCCUUGAAGAGGGACAUGGACAGAGCCUCAUAUGUGAAGUGCUGCCUAUUCUGUAUGUCAUUGAAGCCCUUUCGCAAAUGGGAGGUUGGAAAGGACCUUCCAGCCAUGUUGCGGCUUCUGAGGUCCCUGGUCUUUCCUGGAGGCAAGAAACCCGGCACAAUUACUGAAUGUGGGGAGGACAUUCGCAGUCAAAAAAGUCAUUACAAGUCAGGUGAAUGUGGGAAGGCUUCCAGGCACAAACACACUCCUGUUUACCAUCCAAGAGUCUACACUGGAAAAAAGCUUUAUGAGUGUAGCAAAUGUGGGAAAGCCUUCCGUGGCAAGUACUCACUUGUUCAGCACCAGAGAGUCCAUACUGGAGAAAGGCCUUGGGAGUGCAAUGAAUGUGGAAAAUUCUUUAGCCAAACCUCCCACCUGAAUGAUCAUCGGAGAAUCCACACCGGAGAAAGGCCUUAUGAGUGCAGCGAAUGUGGAAAAUUAUUUAGACAAAACUCCAGCCUUGUUGACCACCAGAAAAUACACACUGGAGCAAGGCCUUAUGAGUGUAGCCAGUGUGGGAAAUCCUUUAGCCAAAAAGCCACCCUUGUUAAACACCAAAGAGUUCACACUGGAGAAAGGCCUUAUAAGUGUGGUGAAUGUGGGAAUUCCUUUAGUCAAAGUGCCAUUCUUAAUCAACACCGAAGAAUUCACACUGGAGCAAAGCCUUAUGAGUGUGGCCAGUGUGGGAAAUCCUUUAGUCAAAAAGCUACCCUCAUUAAACACCAGAGAGUUCACACUGGAGAAAGGCCUUAUAAGUGUGGUGACUGUGGGAAAUCCUUUAGUCAAAGCUCCAUCCUUAUUCAACACCGGAGAAUUCAUACUGGAGCAAGGCCUUAUGAGUGUGGCCAGUGUGGAAAGUCCUUUAGCCAAAAGUCUGGUCUCAUUCAACACCAAGUGGUUCACACUGGAGAAAGGCCUUAUGAGUGCAACAAAUGUGGGAAUUCCUUUAGCCAAUGCUCCAGCCUCAUACAUCACCAAAAAUGUCAUAACACAUAGAGGCCUCAUGAAUGCAGCAAAUGUGGAAGCGCCUUCAACUCAAGAUCUAUCAUCAUUUAGCUCCUGAAAGUCCACACUUAAGUAGAGCCUUAGACCUACAGGGAAAGUGCUGUCUCUGUAGUAUUGUAGCAGUAGAGAGCCUUUGUGAGGGAGCCAUCUGCCUGAAGUUGAACCUCAUUCUUCCUUGUUUCUCUGGUAGAAACCAUCUACCCUCUACCACCUUGCACAGUGGGCACUGGUCACUCCUAUGUGCUAAGACAAGGCAGACAUCUGUGUGUUCUCUUAAGUCUUUGGAGGAAAUCUUGAGCAGUCUAAGCCUUUAGAGAAAAUUCAUUCUUUUUUCUGACUGAUCACAGCAUACGUGUGACCCAGUUUGGGUCAGGAGGGCCCAGCCUUGGUUCUGCUGGACACUUAUGUGCAAGGAUUCCCUUCAUGUAAAUUCUUGGUCUCACAUGACACUUGGUCAUUCUUCCAGCCUCCAUGUCACCACGUGGUGAAUGGCUGCCUCACAUUGCUCCAGUUUGUGCACUAAUAAAAGCCUUAUAUUUGAAUCUACCUGUAGUCUUGGGGUUCUGUUUACUGUGUGGGGUGGCUGGGAGACAGACUUCAACUCUAUAUGAAGGAAUGGAUGGCUUUUGUGGGCCUCUGCAGGAAAGUAAGAUGACAGAGUAAUUCUAAUUCUGGUUUUGGUCAUACUUGCUUUGCUACCUAAAAUCUCCUAGGAAAAAAUGCAAGGUUUUGGUUAUUCUAAUUUGUGGCCUGGAUCCCUAUUCUUUCUGUGAGACUAGAGGUCAUCCUGAGGAGAGGCCAGCUGUUAUGACAAGCAUGUGUGCUUCAGGGAAUAGGACAAUUUUAUUCCAUUGUUUCCAGAGGAUGUCAUAUGAUGCCCAGUGCUGCUGAGAAGCUUUUCAUGGGGUUCUAUAAGGAGGCAUGCCCUGAUAUCAAACAUUCCAUAGGCCGAUGUCACGCAGAAGACAACGCGAGUCACAUGUGAACUGUAAUUGGUACAGAAAUACCUGGGUAUUUCUGUACUGUGUGUACUGUAGCAAACUAGUUGGAAUGUGCCUCUUAUAAAAGUACAUUUACAAAUCUUCCCGUGACUGUGGCUUUGAGCAGUCAUAGGACCUAGAAAUCUGUGUAUGUCCAAUAGCUGAGGUUAUUUUCAGCAAAAAUAAUUAAAGGGUUUUAUUUUUUAAUUCUUGUUGGUUUUCUAGGUUGUUCACCUCAAGUGCAUUGCUGUAGAGGCAGAAAAAGGAGGAUAAAGAUAACAGAAGUCCUAUAGGCCAGGGAUGUAUUGAUAGCUCUUGUGAUUUCCACCAGUGUUGCUGUUGUCUCAAAUUGCCACAGCCUUCAUUGCUUGCCAACAUUUCCUGCAUGGAGGGACUCAUGGUUGCCCUUCCCCAGGCCUGAAGAGAGAGUGCAGUCAACAUGAGAUUGCUAGGCAUUCUGGUUUCUGAAAGUUGGGUGAUCAGAUACUUUAUUGUGAAACAUGUUUUACAAACUUUCUUGAUGUGUAAGUGACAUGCCAUAGUUUACAUCCAUUUAUGGUGUAUAAUUUGAAGAGUUUGUCAUACAAGCCUGUGAAACCAUAAUCAUGAUCAUGAACAUAUUCAUGAUUCACCUCUUGCUGUUUUACAAUCUCUGCGUGUACUUUCCAGGCCUUCAGGAGUCCUGUCAUUUACUUUCCCUACAGGAGAAUAGUUUGUGUUUUCUAGGAUUUUAUGUGAAUUGAAACGUAAAAUACUUACUCCAUUUUUCCUGAUGAUGCACAAUUUUUUUUUUUUUUUUGAGAUGGAGUCUCAGUCUGUCACCAGGCUGGAGUGCAGUGGCAUGAUCUUGGCUCACUCCAACCUCCUCCUGGGUUCCAGCGAUUCUCCUGCCUCAGCCUCCUGAGAAGCUAGGACUACAGGCAUGCACUACCACGCCCAACUAAUUUUUGUAUUUUUAGUAGAGAUGUGGUUUUACCAUGUUUGCCAGGAUGGUCUUGAUCUCUUGACCUCGUGAUCCGCCCGCCUCAGCCUCCCGAAGUGCUGGGAUUACAGGCGUAAGCCACCACACCAGCUGAUGCACAAUUACUUUUAAGAUUUAUCAAUAUUGCUUAUGUGAAUAGUUCAUUUGUAUUGCUGAGAAAUAGUCUGUGGAUAUGUCACAAUUUGGAUAAACAGUUGGAUGCUUUCCAGUUUUGGGCUGUUGCAAAUAAUGCUACUAUGAACAUAGGCAUAUAACUCUUAAUAUGCAGAAAUGCUUUAUUUCUCCUGUGUCAGUAGUACAGUGUACGUGAAUGCGUCACUUUUAAAGACAAGGCCAGACUAUAACCUAACUGUACCAUUUGCAUUCUCAUCAACAGUAUGUGAACCUUCUUAUUUCUCUACAUUCUUGCCAUACUUGGUAUGGUUAGUCUUUUUAAUUUUAGUUGUUUUAAUAGCUGUAUAAUAGCAUCUGUCUGUGAUUUUAUUGCAUUUUUCUGGUAUUUUAUGGUAUUGAACAUUUGAACAUCUUGUAUCUAGUUGCCACCUGUAUAUCCUCUUUGGAAGAAUGUUUAUUAAUGUCUUUUGCUUAUUUUUAAAUGGAUGUUGGUGAUACUUUUUCAUUAAUAAAUAGACGUAUAACAAAGA